CUUUCGGAGCUUGACCAGCAUGUGGAAGGAGAGCUCUCAUGGCUGCAAUAACUUAGGGAGUUCCUACCUGGAUGACACUGGGGUAGGAAGUUUUCUGUUUGUUUUGUUCUGUUUCGGAGGGUCCCGUGCACUUCUCUUGCCUGGAUCAACGUGACUCUUGGUGGUUUUUGCACACCCUGCUCUGUGGGGGAGUGCCCCAACGUGCCUGUCUUAUGUGGCCUCUAUGGACACACUGCUCAGCUGGCAGAGAACAGGGAAGUUUUCUCCCAGCACCCAAAAAGAGAAAGAGGAAACUACUUUUUCUUUCUGGGCUCCUUGCAGCACAAUAGAUCAGGAUAAGCUUCCACAUUUCCUCUCUGGAGUUUCUGGAGUGGUUUCCAGGAAGAAGUUAAACCUUCACCUUUAAAUGGAUGACCAUGUCACAAUCAGGAAGAAACAUCUCCAAAGACCCAUCUUUAGACUAAGAUGCUUGGUGAAGCAGCUGGAAAGAGGUGAUGUUAACGUCGUCGACUUAAAGAAGAAUAUUGAAUAUGCGGCAUCUGUGCUGGAAGCAGUUUAUAUCGAUGAAACAAGAAGACUUCUGGAUACUGAAGAUGAGCUCAGUGACAUUCAGACUGACUCAGUCCCAUCUGAAGUCCGGGACUGGUUGGCUUCUACCUUUACACGGAAAAUGGGGAUGACAAAAAAGAAACCUGAGGAAAAACCAAAAUUUCGGAGCAUUGUGCAUGCUGUUCAAGCUGGAAUUUUUGUGGAAAGAAUGUACCGAAAAACAUAUCAUAUGGUUGGUUUGGCAUAUCCAGCAGCUGUCAUCGUAACAUUAAAGGAUGUUGAUAAAUGGUCUUUCGAUGUAUUUGCCCUAAAUGAAGCAAGUGGAGAGCAUAGUCUGAAGUUUAUGAUUUAUGAACUGUUUACCAGAUAUGAUCUUAUCAACCGUUUCAAGAUUCCUGUUUCUUGCCUAAUCACCUUUGCAGAAGCUUUAGAAGUUGGUUACAGCAAGUACAAAAAUCCAUAUCACAAUUUGAUUCAUGCAGCUGAUGUCACUCAAACUGUGCAUUACAUAAUGCUUCAUACAGGUAUCAUGCACUGGCUCACUGAACUGGAAAUUUUAGCAAUGGUCUUUGCUGCUGCCAUUCAUGAUUAUGAGCAUACAGGGACAACAAACAACUUUCACAUUCAGACAAGGUCAGAUGUUGCCAUUUUGUAUAAUGAUCGCUCUGUCCUUGAGAAUCACCACGUGAGUGCAGCUUAUCGACUUAUGCAAGAAGAAGAAAUGAAUAUCUUGAUAAAUUUAUCCAAAGAUGACUGGAGGGAUCUUCGGAACCUAGUGAUUGAAAUGGUUUUAUCUACAGACAUGUCAGGUCACUUCCAGCAAAUUAAAAAUAUAAGAAACAGUUUGCAGCAGCCUGAAGGGAUUGACAGAGCCAAAACCAUGUCCCUGAUUCUCCACGCAGCAGACAUCAGCCACCCAGCCAAAUCCUGGAAGCUGCAUUAUCGGUGGACCAUGGCCCUAAUGGAGGAGUUUUUCCUGCAGGGAGAUAAAGAAGCUGAAUUAGGGCUUCCAUUUUCCCCACUUUGUGAUCGGAAGUCAACCAUGGUGGCCCAGUCACAAAUAGGUUUCAUCGAUUUCAUAGUAGAGCCAACAUUUUCUCUUCUGACAGACUCAACAGAGAAAAUUGUUAUUCCUCUUAUAGAGGAAGCCUCAAAAGCCGAAACUUCUUCCUAUGUGGCAAGCAGCUCAACCACCAUUGUGGGGUUACACAUUGCUGAUGCACUAAGACGAUCAAAUACAAAAGGCUCCAUGAGUGAUGGGUCCUAUUCCCCAGACUACUCCCUUGCAGCAGUGGACCUGAAGAGUUUCAAGAACAACCUGGUGGACAUCAUUCAGCAGAACAAAGAGAGGUGGAAAGAGUUAGCUGCACAAGCUUUGUCUUCAGAUCAUGUUCUAUAUCAUGUUAGCAGUACAAUAGAGCAGGAGUAUGCAUUUGAUAGAGUGGAACUUUCAGAAGAGACCCCCUGUGUACCAGUGCAAACAAAUGCCUAUCAUCUUUUUUUCUUGAGAGCAGAACUCAUGGGCUGUUCAGCAUCAGAUUUCUGGUGUCUCCUACUCAGGGCUAGGUAAGAGCUCUGUCAGUGUUGAUUAGAAGAAAGUUUGCUCCACUUUGUGGAAGUCUGAUAUUAAUGGUGAGUCCACAUAAAUGAAAUAGUAUUACCCACUAUUUUGUAGUAUGUUUUUGUUUGUUAGCUAAAUGACCUUAAAAAUCUGAUAAAUCACAAAAGGGCAAACUAAAUGUAAGGGUUGUUCCCCAAAAGUUUCUCCUCAUGUUUUAUGUCUGCAUUUGCUAUGCUUUCUGAUACCUCAAACCUAGUCACUUGCUCUAAUUGUACUUUGCAAUAUGAGUAAUGCAUGCAAGAGUUCAUGGGAGUUUUGUGGCUUCUGAAAACUCUGGGACAGGAAGUGUGGAAAUUUGGGAAGUAGAGGUAAUAAUGGGGAAGGGAGUAUUGGGUUGGAUGUUGCACUGUCGAACAGAGAUGAUGGGGCAGAGUAAGCUAAGUCUUUGGAUACAAGGUAUGGAACAGCUCUCAGAGACAGUUCUCUCAUUCUGGUGCCGCUCUCAUCUAGUAGCAGUUUGAUGUGUGACCAGAAUUUGACUGGGUUCAUGUGUAAUGCUCACACCAAGGACAGACUCAAGACUUUGUUAUAUACCCCCAAUAAUUAGCCCCGCUCCAAGUGCUGAAAAUACUUCCAAAUUAUUGGAAGCUCUGUUGUCUUAACCUUACACCUUGAAGAACAGAAAUCCCUUCUUUUGUUACCACUCAUCUCCUCUCUCUCCAAAACCUAUAGGCUUCCGUUCCUCUUGAUUCCAGGUCUCUAUCUAUCUCUCUUCUCAUUCUGCUUCUAAAAUACUCCCAAUUUUUCAGAACAAUUUAGUUCUGAUCAAAAGAUUAAUCAAUUCAACAAAGCAAAAGCCUGAUGGUUUCCCUAAAAUGACGUCUAUAGUUCUUCAAACAAAAAUCACGUACCAUACAUAAUAUGCAAUACUGCAUAUUGUCUGGGUUGAUCAUGGUUUGUCUGUUAUUUUCAAUUUCAUUAGAAUUCCUAUAAAAACUUAAUUUCCUCAUUACCCUCAGGACAUUUUUCAAAAUGUUAAUCACUGUACCUAUGACCUACAUUUGUAAUUAGAAAAUAUCACGAGUUACUGAGUUAGAUGGUUGCUUAUAUUUUUAACAUUUUACGGUUUAUUUAAAUUAUGUUUUUGCUAGAAAAGCUCAUACAUUUUCUCAGUAGGAAACAAAAAAAUGGGAAUAGGUUUUAUAUCACUGGUUAAAAAAUUUAAAAACAAAACUAGAAGUGUUUUUCACUAGAAGUAAGAGAAACAUUUAAAAUUGGUGGGAAAGUAUUAACAUUAUUAAAAGAUCAAAUUUGCCUUAUGAUUAACAUAGUAUUUUAAUAUAUUAUCAUAGUUCACUAAUUAAACUUUAUAUAUUGUUUAUAUUUGAAACAUCUUAAGAUGCAAUAUUUUGUAUUAUGUAUGGUAAAUAAUCUUUGUAAUUAUGUUGGUAUUAAUGCCAAAUCAAAUGUAGAUUCAUAUUCUACUAACUACAUCUUUAUGUUCCAGGAAAUACACUGAGUUUUAUUACAAUCACUAUCCUGUUUAGUCAGACAAAUAACCCUACAAUUUAGAUAUUAUCAUAUCUAAAUCCAAGGUGAGAACUUAGGUCUAAGGCAGCGAAGUAAGUCUCCAGCAUCACAGGUGUAUACAUGUAUUACAAAUGAAUCUAACUUUCUCAUUUCUUUUCACGGUUUCAUAUAGCACACAGAAAAUUAUAUGGUAUAGCUAUGCGGUAGGAGUACAGACAGAAAGAGGAAAGAAUUUCCUGUGAAACCUUACCCCAAAGACUAGCAUAAUUGCUUCAUCAAAUCUACUUCUGUUUAAUCUUAGCACAAUUUAUCCAAUGAGCUUACAAAUGUGCUCAUAAGAUUAGUUAUAUCUCACAGAUAUUUUUAUUUUUAAAUGUUGAAAGUUAUGAAUUUGGGAGUGAAAUUUUUUAUCAUUUAUUCACCCAUUGACCAUCUAUACAAAAAAAAUUACAGCUAACUCUACAAGGAAAGAAUUUUAGUCUGACAAAAGUGAAGCUCACUCAGAGAAACUAAAUUAUUUGUCUAACGUCACAAAACUAAUUUUUGAAAAGGCGGGGCUUUUCAUCUAUUUUGCCCAAAUUCAAAACCAGUAACCUGUAUCAUGUUCUAGAAGUUAAUUAUGAUGGGUUGGUUUAGUUAAAUUCUCUAAACUUCCCUCCAGAGCAAAAAGUGUGCUCAAAAUCUACUGAUGGAAGGAUUCUGACAGCAGCAUAACUUAAGGAUAUUUUAAGUAAUAUUGUGUGUGUGAGUGUGUGUGUGUGUGUGUGUGUAUGAAAGAGAAAGAGAGAGAGGGAGAGUGUGUGUGUGUGUGUGCGUGUGUGUGUGUGUGUGUGUGUGUGUGUGUCUCCUGUCCACUGUAUUUGCAUGGACAACAAAAGUAAGAAGGAAGGUAGAGGGAGCAUGCCUGCAUUCCCAUAGAGAUUAUUAGCUGGCUUGGUGAUGAUAAAAUGUUUUCCCAAGAGGGGCAGGACUAGGACAAGAAAGGAUCUGGGUUGGUAGGAAGAUGAAUUAUCAGAUGAUGUACUCUUUACUAAAUUUGAAAGUAGGGGUGGUCUGUGAAGCUCAUCUGUCUUGGAGUAACUCUUAGAUGUUUACUCAUAGUUAGAUACAGUCAGGAUAUUAGAAGUUAUUUCCAGAAGACUCCACCAAUCCUCUUCAUCCAAGGUAUGCAUUUUGUCCCUCCCAUUUGUUUAACAGGAACCCUAGCAGAUGGUCCUUAUUGAGUAUUAUAGAUUUUUUUUCUUUCUGUGUGUCAUAUCUCAUUGUUGUGAUCAAUAAUUUUAGCCAAUACUGCCUUUACUAUUAUUUUAGUUGUAUCACUCAGAGCUUAUGACAUUUAUUGUGUUGAUAUACAAAAUCCAUGCCACAUUUGUGUGCAAAUAAAUAAAUAUAGCUAAUUCUUAUGGUAUAACUUUCAGCAUUUAUGUUUCAGUAUGUUUUUUUCAAUGUACAAUAUUCUUUCCUUAAAACUGUAUUUCCAUAACUCUACUAAACUGGAGAUGGAAUCAAUGUAAAGUCUGGUAAAUAGUAAAGAGAAGAAACCUAAUUUCAAUGAGUUUAGAAUUGUUCUAAAACCCAUAUGUAGCCAAAAUUGUCCUUCUAUAGUUCAUCUUAAUGCUUAUGAGUUUACCAAAUGCUUAUGAGUUAAAGAAAUUAUUUAUGAUAUUUAUAUUAAAUUAUAAAAAAUAGCAUUAUAUUGCGCAUGAUUAUAACUUGUCAGAUAUACACACACAUACACUUACACACACAUGCACACAAGACUUAAUAAUUUCCUUGAUGCCAUUUCAGGAGAUUAAGGAAUGAUAGAGCACAAUUCCACCUGAAAAUCGUGUUAUAACCUAUGUGACAGCAUUAGCCCUUCCGGUCUGUAAUUCAAUCAGAAAUUUUGUUGUUGUUGUUAGCAUAUUUCAACAUUUUUUAAUAAGAGAAAGAUAUUUUCUGUGGAUAAAGGAAAAGGAAACAUGAUUUUAUUCUUUUUUAUUUUGAAAAUAAAUCACAGAUAGAAUAUCAUUUCUUUACAUAAUAAAAUUCUACAUCCAAAUAUUUGCAUUGCAUACUAUUUGUUAGCAGACAAUAUUAAUAGGUUUCAAGAUAAUCUCUCAUUAGAUUCUGAGAGUGUCUGCUCUAGUUGAUAACAACUAGAGUUGGACUCCAUAGGAAUCCAGGCAACAAUUCAAGUAGAGUAAAAAAUAAGUUGAGUUAUAAAGAAAAAUGAAUCAUCUUAAGAUCACCACUGAUGAAUACAAGAAUCACAAAAGUUUCAAUAGCAAAAGCAAAGUAUAUUAAAAAUUAAGGAAAAUAUGCCAAUUAUGUUUCUCUUCAUAAUUUUACGACAGUAAUUUUUUACAAUCAUGGCUGAUUAUAAAUGAGAAUUACUUUUUUUCAUAACUUCUUUACAGCAUUUUCUCUAAAUUAUUAAA